GGCAUUUCCUGGUGUCUGAGCCUGGCGCGGAGGCUAUGGGCAGCCAGGAGGUGCUGGGCCACGCGGCCCGGCUGGCCUCCUCCGGUCUCCUCCUGCAGGUGUUGUUUCGGUUGAUCACCUUUGUCUUGAAUGCAUUUAUUCUUCGCUUCCUGUCAAAGGAAAUCGUUGGCGUAGUAAAUGUAAGACUAACGCUGCUUUACUCAACCACCCUCUUCCUGGCCAGAGAGGCCUUCCGCAGAGCAUGUCUCAGUGGGGGCACCCAGCGAGACUGGAGCCAGACCCUCAACCUGCUGUGGCUAACAGUCCCCCUGGGUGUGUUUUGGUCCUUAUUCCUGGGCUGGAUCUGGUUGCAGCUGCUUGAAGUGCCUGAUCCUAAUGUUGUCCCUCACUAUGCAACUGGAGUGGUGCUGUUUGGUCUCUCGGCAGUGGUGGAGCUUCUAGGAGAGCCCUUUUGGGUCUUGGCACAAGCACAUAUGUUUGUGAAGCUCAAGGUGAUUGCAGAGAGCCUGUCGGUAAUUCUUAAGAGCGUUCUGACAGCUUUUCUCGUGCUGUGGUUGCCUCACUGGGGAUUGUACAUUUUCUCUUUGGCCCAGCUUUUCUAUACCACAGUUCUGGUGCUCUGCUAUGUUAUUUAUUUCACAAAGUUACUGGGUUCCCCAGAAUCAACCAAGCUUCAAACUCUUCCUGUCUCCAGAAUAACAGAUCUGUUACCCAAUAUUACAAGAAAUGGAGCGUUUAUAAACUGGAAAGAGGCUAAACUGACUUGGAGUUUUUUCAAACAGUCUUUCUUGAAACAGAUUUUGACAGAAGGCGAGCGAUAUGUGAUGACAUUUUUGAAUGUAUUGAACUUUGGUGAUCAGGGUGUGUAUGAUAUAGUGAAUAAUCUUGGCUCCCUUGUGGCCAGAUUAAUUUUCCAGCCAAUAGAGGAAAGUUUUUAUAUAUUUUUUGCUAAGGUGCUGGAGAGGGGAAAGGAUGCCACACUUCAGAAGCAGGAGGACGUUGCUGUGGCUGCUGCAGUCUUGGAGUCCCUGCUCAAGCUGGCCCUGCUGGCCGGCCUGACCAUCACUGUUUUUGGCUUUGCCUAUUCUCAGCUGGCUCUGGAUAUCUACGGAGGGACCAUGCUUAGCUCAGGAUCCGGUCCUGUUUUGCUGCGUUCCUACUGUCUCUAUGUUCUCCUGCUUGCCAUCAAUGGAGUGACAGAGUGUUUCACAUUUGCUGCCAUGAGCAAAGAGGAGGUCGACAGAGGCCAAGAAAACCAUGGAGGAGCAGUGGACCUUGGUGUCCCUGCUGAGCACAAGCCAGCAACAAGGACCUGUCCCCCCAGGCUCCACGGCAUCCUCAGCCACAGACAAGCUCAGCCGCUGGGAGUGUGCACCUGUCACAACCAUCAAGAGACAAGGGAUGGGUGUCAGAGGUGUCUGGGAGAUGAAAGAUGCAUGGAGCACUCCAAAUGGCCGCAUGCUUUCUAAACACACAACUCACCAGGAUUUCAUCUGCAACUCAGAUUCAAUCGGCUAAGUGGGGAAGAAGAAAGUAUGUGGUUGUCAUGGCAACACCAAAUUGCCCAGGACCAGGUUGGUCUCUAAGCAGGGGAAGGGAAGGGAGUGGAGCUGAGCCUCUGUCUCUGUGGUGGGGAUGUUCUGGAGAACGGGGCCCAAGGGUCAGGCCCGACAUACACCUGUGGGGCAAGGGGCCUUGUUCUCACUACCCCUGCUCAGGGCUGAGGGCCUGAGCCAUGCAGUAUUAUAUAAAGGGUUGACUCGGGGCCCUCACUCUGGGGCUGGGGCCCAGACUACUCCAGCAUGCAAGUUCCAGAGCCAGCCUCUUGCUAAGGGCCAGUCCCUGCUUCUCCCCACGGGCUAGACCCACCCCAGAGCAGCUCAGAUUUGGUGCCUGCUUCUCUUCUUGCCCCCUAGUCCUAGCUGUUCCUGGCAGAGCUUCUGUCUUGAGCUUGGCCAUGGAUGUGGACACAGCCUGGCACAUACCCUGAGUGCGGUCUAAAGGAUCAAGGGACACAAAGCCUCACCCAGAGAGUGCCAAGCAAAGCUGAUACUUCUAUUCAUACGCAUGCAGUGCUCAGCCUGGCCUCCUUCUUCCCACCAAGAAUGAAGUGGAGCCAGCAGAGGGGUUGCCCUGCAAUGUGGUCUCUGCCAACCUGGGCCCAGGCCUAGCUGGAUAGGUGGUAGGAGAGAGGGCUGCUCAAGUAGGAAGGAGGUGAGCAUCAGGACCCUCCCCUCCCCUGGACCUGCCUUAGCCCUGUUUUGAUUCUGACCAUCCAGUGCUCUGGGGACCCUGGAAAAGGUCCUGGCUCCAAGGUCCACCUGACCAGCCAAGCCUGGCACAUCCAUCUCUGUGGUCCCAGGAUCUGGCCACAGGAGGGCUCCUGGACACGUAAUACAUGAAUAGAUGGAGUGACAUAAAGAAUUAAUCAGUGGGUGACUUAGGCAGUGAGAACUAGGAGCAGAAGAAAUGAAAGAGACCAGGUUGGGAGGGGGGAUGCUGGUAGGGCCAGGUUUAGGGGAGCCUUAAAUGCCAGGCUGAGAGGGGGUGUUUGUCAGGCUCCCCCACACCCAGCUUCUGCCCUGGCCCUGGGACAAUUUCCGUCUUCCAGAGGGGCCAGUAGGGAUCCUGGCAGAUGUGGCCCUGAUCACCUGAUCCCCUCUCAGAGAGACAGAGACCCCAGGGCCCAUCCCCCAGAGCCUGGCUCACCUGGGCCCUCGCAGGGCCUGCCUCACCGGGGCCCCGCAGACCUAACUGCUUCUGCUUCAUGGUCUGUGGGUUUUCCCAGUCGUCCAAUUAGUGCUAAUUGGAAGCAGGAAGUGUGUGCAUGUGUGGGGUGGGCCUGGAACUCCGAUGUCCUUGUCAGAACUUCGAAGCCCUGUGCUUCCUGGGACAGGCUCUUCCCUAGAGCUUUGUGGUCUCCCGCAGGGCUGGGUAGGGUUGUUGGGAGCUCCCCGAGCAUUGGGUAUACUGGCUCUGUGCACAACGGGGCCUCUGCUCUCCAGAGGGCUCAGGCUCUCACCGGCCACCUCUUACCCCAGGUGCCAGUUGCCCCCAGGGCAAGGCAAGCUCAUCCUUUUCACUGCCAAAUCCUCUUCGCCCGGCACAGAGCUGCGGCUCUUCACAGUUUCACUCUAACAACGAAGGGAAUGAUGGGCUCAGGGCCUGGAAGAGAGGCGCAGAGGGGGCCUCCUGAACCCCUCACUGACCCUUGGUCCAGCCUCAGCCCGUGGCUCCAUAAAGGCAAGGAAAGGCCUGCUUUAUCUGACUGGCCACACACUUGUGCUUCCCUUGGGGGACAAAGGGUGCAGAGGCGCUUCCACAGAGGCGGGACUUCCGCUUACUUUCCCUCCUCCCCGUUUCCCCGCCCCCUCCACUUGCGGCACAGGUGGGGGUGUCCAGAGGCAAAGCCCCUUUUGUGUCAAGCCCCAGCCCAGGUUCUCUCCUCACCCACAGAUGCUGGUGCGCAGUCUGACGGCAGAGGCUGUAACGGGGGAAGCAUGGGAUGUGGGCACAUGGGGGAAGGCCCCGGAACCCAGCCUGGGCAGAGGCCGGUGCCCCACCAGGCUCUCUCUCUGCAGUGUUAUGUCAAUCAUUGCCCACAGGUGCCCUCGACCUGGACACCGUCAGGCCUCCUUCGCGGUGGGCUGAAACCCUGUGGCACAGCCCAGGACCACCCAGCCCCACGGGCUGGGGGCUCACAUCUGGAAGCAGGGCCCCCCAGGACUCAAAGGUGCUCGGAGAUGAAGAUUGCUGGGUGUCAGCUCAUGGGGCCAGCCUCGGCUUCACCCCCAGGAAAUGCCUGCUUGUUGCUGUGCGGCAGGCACUAGAGCAGGCAGAGAGGGCGGUGGGCUCCUCUGAGGUCGCGGGCGGAGCCCUGUGAGGAGAGACCUGGCCGCCGGCAGCCACUAGAGGGCAGGACCCUCCUGUGUGUUUCCUCCAAAGGGUUGUUGAGCAGAUGAGCGGGACUGACAGGAAACAAUGGAGCAGCCGCCCCAGGGUGCAGUCACCACAAGCCUGCUAGAAGGGCUCAGCGGAGGCUGCGAUGCGUCCGAAAGUCCACUGGACCCUAGACCUUAAAUGGCCUCCCUGAGCCUUUAGGCUUUUACUUCCUGGGAGCCCAGCCCUGAGCCAACAGAGACAGUGCCUGGCUCCUACAUUGGCAGAGAGUGACAAGUCAGUGUCCCCUUCUUACAACAUCAGUGGUAGAGGAGCAAUUAGGAGAGCAGGUCCUCCAGCUUCUUCCAGGUGCAGUGUGGAAACAGAGGCAGAGAAGAACUCACCUGACCGCACCUACGAGGUGGGUAGGGACAGAUACUUCUGAGAGUGAACCAUCAGCCAAGCACGCCCAGCAGCCCUGGGGGGUCAGUGCAUGUUGUCGGGUGCUACUUUUGCAGUUGGGGAAACUGAGGGUCAAGAGAGGCUGUCAUUUGACUGAAGUCCUACAGCAAGGGUGGACCAGGGUUCCCGCCCGGGCAGGAUGAUGCUGAGCCUGCAUGCAGGCUCCCACGCAGCCUUAUCACAGCCUCAUGUAGAGACGACCUCCUGUGACCUCGCUGACAUGAGUGUGAGUGUGUGGGGACCCUGGCUGCCGCAGCAGGAAUGAGGCAGCCUCUCUGCAUCCUGACACUCCCAGGCAGAGGCCUGUCCUUCAUCUGGACCUACCAACAGUGACGCCAGGAGCAGCUGCCUCUAGGACACGUGUUCCCCUGGGCCAGAGGAACUAUGUGAGGAACCCAUGGUGCAUGCCAUGACAACCCUCCUUUAGGGCCUCUUGAGGCCACAGUGGUGCUAAACCCAGGAAGUGGGUGCCAAUUCAGGGGACCAUUGGCAGCCCUGCUGCCCCUCACUGGGCUGUGCCUGCAGUCACGGGAGGCAAGGACCUGCUUUUGAGUCUUUGGCUUCACCUUGUUCUUACAGCCAGACUUGGGGCUCUCUACCUGGGGCUGGGGAUAGGUAGUUCUCAGCCUGGGCAGCCCCAGGAGCUGCUAAGUGUCAUAUCCCUGGGGAAGGCCUGAGCAGUUUGAGGCUGAUUUUGGUUGUCCCAAUACUGCUGGGAACCACUGGGGAAUGAGAGUGUCUUGGGGACCUAUUCCUGGAGCCUGAGUCUAAGCUGAGCUGUGGCUCAUAAGACUAAAUUGCAUGGAGACCCAACAUGGCUGCUGGGCCCGUCAAGGGCUGGUGUCUGCUCUGGGAGGUAGCCCCAUGGCUGGAUCUUUCUCUAUGUCCCAGGUCGGCCCCUGUGACCUGGGGCCAGUGUGCUGAAACCUGUGAGGAUCAGGCAUAGCGAGGAGGGUGGCCCCAUAGGUAGGCCCAUACAAGGGACUUGGGCAGAGUCCUGUCCUCCAGCUAAGUAUCUGGGGCACCAACCUCACAGACUGCAGAGUUCACUCUCAUUAGCGCAGGGGUCCUCUCAACAGCUUCAGUGACCAUAGGGAUCGGUGUACCCAUUUCACAGAUGGGGACACGCCGGCUCAGGUCUUACCACCCUUUGCCAACAGCUUCUUCACUGGUCUCCUUAGCUUCCGUUUUCCCUUUUCCUUCCUUGUUUUAAGCUUUCAAAAAAAAUUUUUAGGCUGGGUGUAGUGUCUCCUGCCUGUAAUCCCAGCACUUUGGGUGGAUUGCUUGAGCCUAGGGGUUUGAGACCAGCCUGGGCAACUUAGUGAGACCCCACCUCUACAAAAAAUUCCAGAAUUUUCUUUCUUUACUAAUUUAAACAUUUUGGCUGGGCUUGGUGGCUCAUGCCUGUAAUCCCAGCACUUUGGGAGGCCAAAGUGGGCGGAUCAUCUGAAUCAGGAGUUCUAGACCAGCCUGGCCAACAUGGUGAAACCCUGUCUCUACUAAAAAUACAAAUUAGCCAGGCGUGGUGGCAUGUGCCUGUAAUCCCAGCUCCUUGGAAGGCUGAGCCGGGCUGGUCUUGAAUUCCUAACCUCAGGUGAUCUGCCCACCUCAGCCUCCCAAAGUGCUGGGAUUACAGGUGUGAGCCACCGCACCUGGCCAAAAAAAAACUUUUAAAAUUAUUUAGUGGCUUAUUAUAUAAGAAAUACAUGAAUGCAUUUUUACUUUAAAAACAUAAUACACCCAGCAGUUUGGGAGGCUGAGGCAGGUGGAUCACCUGAGGUCAGGAGUUCGAGACCAGCCUGGCCAACAUGGUGGAACCUUGUCUCUAACUAAAAAUACAAAAAUUAGCUGGGUGUGGUGGCGGAUGCCUGUAAUCCCAGCUACUCGGGAAGCUGAGGCAGGAGAAUUGCUUGAACUCGGGAGGCGGAGGUUGCGAUAAGCUGAGAUCGUGCCACUGCACUUCAGCCUGGGCGACAGAGUGAGACUCCGUCUCAAAAAAAAAAAAAAAAAAAAAAAAAACCAUAAUACAGGGCUGGUCAUGGUGGCUCACACUUGUAAUCCCAGCAUACUUCUGGGCUCAGGCAAUCCUCCCACCUUGACCUCCCAAAGUGCUGGGAUUACAGGCGUCAGCCACCGCACCCAGCCUGUUUUGAUUUUUUUCAAGAGACGAGGUCUCACUAUGUUGUCCACACUGGUCUUGAACUCCUGGGCUCAAGCUAUCCUCCUGCUUGUGCUUCCCAGAGUUUUAGAUUUUCAGGCAUGAGCUAUCACACCCAGACUUAUUUUCUCCUUUAUCCCCAACCACUGCAGUUAGGUUUGGGUUGGGAUGGGGGCAGGUGGGAGAUGGGGGAAGCCAACCUCCAAGCAGGGCAGGAAACAUCUAGCCAGCCCCAUCUUCCUGAAUCCACAGCUAGGGUGCCUCCCAGAGAGCCUGCUCUGCUGCAGGGCACAGUGGGGAGUAGUCUGUCUCCAUAGACACACAGCAUCCCAAAGCCAAACAUUUCCCUCCUCAGUCCUUGUAAUUGCCACUAGGCUGUGCAUAUAUGGGAAACCCACAGGGUUUACCUCAUCCCCUAUUGCUGGACAUCCAGGCUGUUUUCAGCGGUGCUGUUACAGCUCACUGCAGUGGCCGCCACAGUGCAGGUCUCUGCCAGGCUCUCUACGGGGAGGCGCUGGGAAGUAGAAUUGCUGAGCUGGGGGGCAGGGGCUAAGUCACCCUCCAAAAAGCCUGUGCCCACCCCCAGCAUAGGCACUUGUUGUACUAACACUUUGCUAAAACCUCUCUCUUCAAUGGGAAUUUGUCUCAUUGCUUAUGAGUUUGCUUAUCUUUUCUUACUGAGUGAUCAUUUUUAUUUCCUUUUUUUUCUUUUUCCCCCUCACCUCUCUGAAUUUUAUUUAUUUCCUUUUACCAUGAAGAAUCUGCUUAUAUCCUUUCCCCAUUUUUCCACUAUGGUUUUUAUCUUUUCCUUAUUCAUUUGUAGAUCUUUAUACAGAUGCUCUUCAACCUGCUGUGGAGUUUCAUCCCAAUAAACCCUUUACAAGUUAAAAAUACUGUAAAAUGAAAAUGUAUUUAAUAUGCCUAACCUACUGAACAUCAUAGCUUAGCCCAGCCUGCCUUAAACAUGCCCACAACACUGACAUUAGCCUACAGUUGGUCAAAGUCACCUAACACAGUCUGGGCACAGUGGCUCACACCUAUAAUCCCAGCACUUUGGGAGGCUGAGGAGGGCGGAGCACUUGAGGUCAGAAGUUCGAGACCAGUCUCGCCAACAUGGUGAAACCCCGUUUCUACUAAAAAUACAAAAAUUAGCCACGCGUAGUGGCACAUGCCUGUAGUCCCAGCUACUCAGGAAGCUGAGGCAGGAGAAUCGCAUGAACCUGGGAGGCGGAGGUUGCAAUGAGCUGAGAUUGUGCCAUUGCACUCCAGCCUGGGCAACAAAAGUGAAACUCCAUCUCAAAAACAAAAACAAACAACAAAAUGUCACCGAACACAAAGCCUGUUUUAUAAUAAAGUGUUGAAUAUCUCAUGUAAUUAUCAAAUAUUGUGCUCAAAGUGAAAACCAGAAUGGUCGUAUGGAUACUUGAAGUAUGAUUUCUACUAAAUGUGUAUGACUUUUGCACCAUUGUAAAGUAAAAAAAAAUCCCAAGUUGAGCCAUAUAAGUCAGGGACCAUCUGUACAUUCUGGAUUUAAAUCCUUUGUUGUAUUUUCUCGCUUCCCUUUGCCCCACCUGGAGAGGUUGACUCUAGAGGGAGUGCAGGGGACAGGGCCAGGACCAGGCUUUCUGCCUGGCUGCAGCUCUUGGAUGUUAUGUUGGAAAAUGUCUAACCCUGGCUAGGUGGAGACACAAUGGCCAGGUGACUUUUCUGAAAGCCUCUGUUCUGUCACCUGUAAAGUGGACAGAAUACUGCCUACCUUGCAGGGUUGUGGUGAGGAUUAAAGGAACCCACCCAUGGACAGGUCAUCUGAUGAGUGCCACACACAUGUGAGGUGGACAGCUGCUGGGCAGGAGGCACCGUGUCGAGUAGGUGCCCAAUAAACGGUGACUGUGGUCUCUGUGCCCAGUGAGUGUAUGUGGGUACCUUGGUGGGGGGGGUCUCUCCUGCAGAGCCAGUGCUCAGAAGUUUAGCAUGGAUGGGGGGCAGUCUGAGACAGGGCUGGUGCUUGGAGGAAGGGAGAAGUGGAUGGGCUGAGCUUAGGGAGAAGACACCACAAGGUUGGCUCAUAUUGGGUGCAGUUGUGAGGGUCUACUAAGGUCAAGCCCUGUCCCCUCCUGCAUCAGGAUCCCCAAAGGAAAGUGUUGGGCUGACUUCCUCCAGCCAGGUUGGCUACAGCUGACCCUCUGGUCCCACUCCUGCCAGGCAGUCCUGGGGCCUCAGAAAAGCCCUUUGGAGGUGACAUGUGGUCCAGCCCACUUGAGGGCAUGACUUGGCCUUGGCUGUAAUCUGCUGAAACUAAAUAGGAGGUAUAUUUAUGAGUUGCCAUAAAAGGCACUGACAUACUGGUGAUAAAAGCCACCAAAAUCGCCCUGCUGUAAACUGCCAUUUACAUGUUUAUGACCUUAUUCCCCAGCCAGUGGGUUAGAUAUUCCCAUUAUCACUGACCAGGAGGCUCAAUUCUCAGCCAGGGGCCUGCAGGGUGAGUUGAAAAAAGGAAGCACUAAUAUGCAGGCCCAGGGCCACUGCCUGCUCCUCCUUGCAGCUGCUCCCUCCCAAGAGACUCCUCCUAUCGAGCAUACCCUGGAGGCUUAUUCUCUUACUGAGGAGUAACUUACAUUCGGUACACUACAGCAAUCAUGAAUGCAUAAUACAGCUCAAUGAAUUUUACAUAGGUGCACACCUGUGUAACCGUGACCCCGAGCAAACUUCCUCACCCUAGGAGAUUCCCUUGUGCCCCUUCCCCGCCAAUGUCCCCUAGCCCAGAAGUAACCACCGUUCUCACCUCCAUCAUCAGAGAUCAGUUUUGCUGGCCUAGAAUUUCACCCAAAUGUCGUCAUACAUGUGUUUUCUUCUGUGUGUGGCCUCCUUUCAUCAAUACAAUGUUUUUUAUUUUUGUAUAUUUUUUGAGACAGGGUCUUGCUCUGUUCUCCUUCCGUAGUGCAGUGGGGCGCCAUCACGGCUCGCUGCAGCCUCCAACUCCCAGGCUCAAGUGAUUCUCCCACCUCAGCCUCCCAAGUUGUAGCUGGGACUACAGACAUGCUCCACCGUGCCCGGCUGAUUUUUUCUAUUUUUUUGUUUGUUUGUUUGUUUUUAGAGACAGGGUUUCACUAUGUUACCCAGGCUGGUCUCUAACUCCUAGGCUCAAGCGCUCCGCCCGCCUCGGCCUCCCAAAGUGCUGGGAUUACAGGCGUGAGCCACUGCGCCCAGCCAAUAUAAUGUUUUCCAGAUUCCUCCACGCUGCCCUGUGUAACAGUUGUUCUUUCUUUUUUAUCGUUGAGUAGUUGUCUCCAUUGUAUGGAUGGAUAGGCCACACUGGUUUAUUUAUUCUCCUAUUGAUGGAUAUUUGGGUUGUUUCCAGUUUUUGGCUACUAUGAAUAAAGAUGCUAUGAAUAAUCCUGUGCA